AUACUUGCGCGCCGACGCCGCCGCUCGCUUGUGAAACUGGAAGGCUGCCAUGGCUAGCCCAGCCGCCUCCUCGGUGCGACCACCGAGGCCCAAGAAAGAGCCGCAGACGCUCGUCAUCCCCAAGAAUGCGGCGGAGGAGCAGAAGCUCAAGCUGGAGCGGCUCAUGAAGAACCCGGACAAAGCAGUUCCAAUUCCAGAGAAAAUGAGUGAAUGGGCACCUCGACCUCCCCCAGAAUUUGUCCGAGAUGUCAUGGGUUCAAGUGCUGGGGCCGGCAGUGGAGAGUUCCACGUGUACAGACAUCUGCGCCGGAGAGAAUAUCAGCGACAGGACUACAUGGAUGCCAUGGCUGAGAAGCAAAAAUUGGAUGCAGAGUUUCAGAAAAGACUGGAAAAGAAUAAAAUUGCUGCAGAGGAGCAGACCGCAAAGCGCCGGAAGAAGCGCCAGAAGUUAAAAGAGAAGAAAUUACUGGCAAAGAAGAUGAAACUUGAACAGAAGAAACAAGAAGGACCCGGUCAGCCCAAGGAGCAGGGGUCCAGCAGCUCUGCGGAGGCAUCUGGAACAGAGGAGGAGGAGGAAGUGCCCAGUUUCACCAUGGGGCGAUGACAAUGUUUGCCACAGCCUCUGCCUGGAACCUGGCUCGUGCUGUGACCAGAAGGGAAAGGCGGCUGUUUGGCUCUUUCUCCCCCGCAAGGACCCGCUGACCCGCUGGAUGGAGAGCAAAGGAGACCCCUCCCGAGCCGCUCACAGUCCUGUAUUUGGCAGGUUUGGGAGCCUGAGGGGCCAUCUCCCUGACACUCAGAGGCACUGCCUUGCAGACACCAUCCGUGCUCCUGGUAAAGGGGGACAGAGAGCCUCACCUUGCCACAUAUUUGAACAGUGAUGAGUUUGGGGCUGGUUUCUGGGAAGGGAACGUUUAUUUAGUAAAGAGCAGAACACCCUUGCGUUUUGUUGGGACAUGUGGACCGUGAGUCGCAAACACUCUGGAGAAGGCUGAGAUGCCACCAUUCCCACGGGGACUGAAGACACAUUACGUGGACCUGGUCCCAGGCUCAGUGAGGAGAUGGCCUCAGCUGUGGGGCUGGUCCAUGUUGCCCACUCACUCCAGUGGGAAGUGGGGACCACGCCAUAGAGGGUCUGCUCCCACUGCAGCUCCCGGUGCUCUCGUGUUCUGGGAAGGCCUGGGUGUGUGCACAAGGAGGCCCGGGCCAGGGACUUCACCAGGGGCUGGGUCACAAGGGCACAGGGUGUGUGGAAAGCGCUGUGGGGGAAGAGCCGGUCACCGGAGAGUGAGCAGGCGGAGACUCCAAGCUGGGCUGAGCCAGAGCAGAAGGCGAGGGAUUCCCAGCCGGACGGGGGUUCUCUCACCAACAGCUGUGAUUUCAUCCCGAAGUGGAAGGGGGUCUAAACAGAACAGGCUGAGAGAGGCGGGACUGGGUCAAGUGGGUGGAGCUCCUCCUUGCAUGACUGCAACUGUCGGGGCUUUCCGCCGGCUCACAGCAGUUGGGGCCAGCGGGGAGAAGAGAGGCGGAACUGCUGUGUCCUCAUGUGGCGCAGCCUCAAACUGGCAUCCAGGCACUGGGCCCAUGCAGAGAAGGCACCUGCAGAGAGCAGGGCAGCCCGGCGCAGGGGCAUGCGCCUAGAAUCCCAGCUACUCGGAAGGCCAAGGCAGGAGGACCGCUUGAGUCCAGGGAUUCAAGGCCAACCUGGGCAAUAGAGCGAGACCCUGUCUCUUAAAAAACGAUGAUGAUGAACACAGAGGACGGGGCACUGUGCUGGGAGCCAGGGGGCCUGGGAGGAGCCGAGACCAGCCUUUUACCUCGGGGUUUUGAGGCCAACAGGGACGACAGAGACAGUUUCUAGUUAGAGCCUUGGCUCCAUUUUUGGAUGAUUUAGCCCCGAGUUCCUGAGUCUAUUUUAUGCCCCUUACGUACUUUGAUAGAACUAAGGAAAUAGUGGUUUUGAGUGAAGGGAAAGGAAACCCAGAAACAUUUUACGUUGCUUUUACUUCUGUAGUGUAGAUUGCCCCGGCCCCUCUCUGAGCCCUGUAGCAUCUGUGAUAGCUUCUGUCCCUUCAUCGGUUCAUGUCACAGGGAUUUUCUUUCCCAGGAAGCGGACACGGAGAGUCAGCCCUAAUAAAUGAGCACAUGCCCUGGCUGUA